UGUAAUAUAACAUAUAGUAUAUAUGUCAAAUACCACAUAUCAUAUAUCACAUAUUUAUGUCUCCUCCCCAACUCUGUGCUACCUCUUCUUGAAUACCUCAUAAUUUUCUUUUAAUAGUACUCAUAAACCAUGUAUUAAAAUGUAACUUAUAGAAUUAGGGGUUUUAUGGCUAUUUUAUGGGAUAUUGUUUUCCAAACCUACGUUUCUCCCCUCACUGCCCCAGCUCCUUCUUUUGAUAAUCAAGAAAAAAUUUAAUUUUCUUAUAUAUCAAAACAAUUAUUUAUUGCUUGUUUGUUUUUUCCCAUUAUUUCUGAAGAUCCAAUGCAUCUGAGCCUAGAGACUUAAACAUAUAUAUGUGCUUACUUUUUUUUUUUUUUGGCUUACCUUCAAUCUUCUUAUUUUUUCAGUUUCCUACUAAAAUGAACCAUUUAAGGUAUCUUUUUUGCAGUUUGGAGAGUAUUCUUCUUGAUGAAAAUUACAAAAGAAACAAGGAGAGACAUUGUUUCUCUUCCUCUUUGUCUAAUGCUAACAUUGCACCAUCUGGCUCAAGCUGUGGGUCUAGCCUUUCCUGUUCUUCUUGCCUCGAACAUAACCAAAAACGCAUUUUGAUAAGCUCAGCAUUUUCUCUGCAGCUUUAGCUCAUCUUUUGCUCCUGCUUUAUUGAUGUUAUCCUGAUAUCUGAUCAUGAUGCUGACAAACAAAUUGGGCUAGGAAGAGUUUUAAAAACUUGCCACCACCUGGUGAAACUGAACCUUAAACAAACAGCAACACUGCUGGUAACACUGGCAAGUUCCACUGAGCGCUUAUUCCCAAAAGGCAAAUGGGGGCUAAGAGACAGGCUUGAUCACUUGCAAUGGAAAUACAUAUGAGCUCUGUGCACAAUGUUGCUAUCAUACAGCAAAGAACAUUCUUUAGCCAAUCUCUGUAGGAUGGCUCUGAAAUAGCAUCUGUGCCUGAGAAUAGCAACACUGUCCAAUGUGUCAAUGUUCAGUGCUUAGCUUAAUGCCAGGCACAUAGUAGGUACUCAAUAAUAUUUUGUUUAUUGACAGCAGGAGGACAAUGCAUGUUGUAGGAGAGGAAAAAGAUUAAUUCCUUCCAGUCACAUGAAGACUGAAGCUUAGUAUAUGGAUUUAAUUUUUCAUAUUAUCUUUGGACUGAUUUGAUAUAUUUUACUUUAAAGACUUACCACUUUGAUCCACAGGGAACCAUUAGUGGUGAAAACAUGGAAUAUGCUUCUUGGAAAAUGCAUUGCUUCAACAGAUUAAAGGCACAUAAGCUGGAGCAAGUAUGCAAACCUUCCUAGUUUGAACUAAAAAGAAAAGAAACAAAGGAAGGAAUUAAUGGAAAUUUUCAAAUCUAAGUCUCUUCUGAUAUUUCAAGGAAAACCUCAGGAAGUGAAUCAAGAAAGAAUAAGACUAACCAAAUCUUCUUGGUUAAAGAUACUGUGAUACUAUGAUUCAAGUUCAAACAUCCAAGAAAGGAAUCUACUAUUUUCUUUUUAACAUUAGUUAUUAAAACUGUCUUAAUACUCUCUAUUAGCUUACAGGAAAGUUAAAAUAUGAGUCAAUAUAUGAUGUACUACAGGGUUUUACAGAAAUAAAGUUAUUUAACAACUAUCUCAAUAUUGUGUGUAAUAAUCUCUAAAUUUGCUCAAGUAGUUUUGGAAAUAGUCAUGGCAUAAAUGAUAGGUUAAUUUAUCAAUUUUCUGCUUAUUUGUAUGGAUUCUAUAUCUCACUAUUCAUAUUUGCUAAGCAUCCAUUCAAAUUAAGACCCUUUUUUGGUUAUAAAAAGCACACAAUCAUAUGAGCUACGUUAACUGGUUACUAGCUGGAAGGGAGAGGUUUACCUCAGUCACAGAUCCAACUUCAGUGCAGGGUUUGCUAUUUUUAAUCACAGAACUUAGAAGCUUAAUUCAGUUAAAAAGAGAGGAAGUUGUCAAGGGAGGGUUGCUAAAAGUUCAUGCUAAAUUUGCUUAGAACCAGAUUGUGUUCAUUAAUAUUUAUACAUCUAUGGUUGGGAAGGGGUGAUUGUGCUUCUUUAAAAACACUGGGUAUUCAUUUUCCAUGUAUGGCACAGCCUUCUGAUUAGGGAAGGUGGGUUUUCAUUGUACAAUCAAUGGAGAUACAGAUGGAAACCAUCUGGCGCCUCAUCCCCUUUUUGUCAAAAACCUUGUCUUGUCUCUCACAUGUCAAUGAUGAAUGGAAGGAUUUCAAACUCUAGCUGAACAAUGCAGUUUGAAUCCCUCAGCUAGCCAAGGGGUUUUUGGCAAGCAUCGAUGAGCUUAAUAUUUUAAAGAAACCAGCAAUCAUUUUAAUUCAUUAGUUGAAGCCUGUUGUUCUAGACAGUGUUUUUGAUUUGUAUUUUGGGCACUGGCUUUGUUUUUGAUUCACAAGCGUAUUCCAUAUGGGUAUAUUUUCUUUUAUACAGUGUAAAUCAUGGGGAUAAAAGUGGGAGUUUCAUCUGAUAAAAUGACCAAAAUGCUGAGAGAUUCUUUUAAUUAUCUUUUGCAUUAAUUAUGAUUCAUAUUAAGUGUUAAGACCAAAAAUUUUCUUGUGAGCUAGUACAGAGCAUGAAUCAGAGAACACAGAAUUUAGUUAACCCAGCUAUAGACAAUUAAUCUAAAAAUCAAUUCAGUGUUCUGCUUUGUGAGAGGAAACGACAUAAACCUGUCUUAGAGCAUCUCGGGUACACUAUUUUUAUGGCUUGUCUGCUGAAGGUGGGUUUCUAGGAUGGAAGCAAAAAAAUCGAUUCACAUGGCUAGCUUUGCAGUCAUUAUUCAGCUAACAAAAGCCAGAUUGGUUUUCCUGCCCUUCACAUUUAAUAAAAUGAGGUGAAUCACCAAAAAAGCAAGUUGAUGCUGGAGCCUUAUUCAGAAACUCAUUUCCAGAGUAUGUCCUGGGUUUGGUAGAGAUUCAACCCAAUUUUAUAUAACUACCAAUAUUGUGGUGGCCCCUAUAGCAGUUAUAGUCCCUACCAGUGACAUUUGUGAGGGACUGUGGUUAAGAAAGGACAUAACAUAAAGUUAUUUUAUUUAAUUAUAAUGAUUACUGUGCUUAUUACCUGCCAGCUACUCUUCUAAAUGCCAGAUAGAUUAUCGAUAGGUAGCUAUAUGGAUGACAGGUGAACAGGUAUCAUGGAUAGAUAGACACAUAGAUAGAUAGGUAGGUAAAUAGGUUUUACUUAUUUAAUCCUUACAACCACCCUGAUAGGUAAGUUAUAUUAUUUUCAUCAUUAUACAGGUAAAGAAAGUAAGGACCAGAGGGAUUAAGAACUUUGCCAAGACAAUAGCUAUUAAAUGGUAGAGUGGGAAUUCAAAUCCAGAAAGGCUCUGAAAUCUGUGUGCUUAACUCUUACACUUAUCGUUUCUCAUAGUCAUCAUAUGAGGUAGAGGUUAUUUUUGUUAUUUCUGUUUGAAAGAUGAGGAAACCAAAGCACUGAGAGGUUAAAUUACUUGCCCCAGUCUAGGUUGUCCAACUGGUAGCCUGUAGAGCCAGGACUUGGGCUUUCUGUGUCUCAUUCUCUUUGCACAAUGGAAAAUUUAGAAUAAUCCCCCAUAGGCACCACAAGAUCUCUAAUAAUCAGAGAAGGACUAAAUUUUGUUCAGCAUAGCUCAGGCCUAGGAAAGGAAAAUGGAUACUGAUUGUUGCCAGAUUUGCAAUAGUGUAAUCCAACCAAAUUAUUUAUAGUUCUUAUUAAUAAUAAAUUGAAAUUAACUCAUUCUGAUAUUACUCAAUUGAGUAUUUAUGAUAUUUUUCUUACCUCCAAUUGUUGGUAAAAGUAAUCCUUAAUAUAUAAGGAGCAUUUACAAUUCAAUAGGAAAAAAAGGUGCGUACUCACAUUUUUUUAAAAAUGGACAAAUAAUGAGAAUAAAGAAAUACAAAUAGGCAUUAAACAAAAACACAAUGGCAAAAAGAUUUAACUUCAUUAAAGAAAAACCCUAUGAAGUCAUCCUUGUAUUAAAUUGACAAAGAUUAAACAAACUAGUAAUAUAUAGCAAGAACUGUGGUACAAAAGAAUUGGCAUUCUCAUCCCUUGCUAAGGGUGCAGUUUUUUUUAAGGACAAUUUGUCAACGUGCAUCACUAGCCACUGUAUGCUUUGAUCCAGCAAUACCACAUCUUGAAAACUGAUCCCAAGAAUGGCAUCAUGGAUGUAAACAAUUUUAAAAUAAUUAAUAGGAACAUUAUUUAUAAAAUCAAAAAUUAUAAUCAACUGAUAAAGGAUGGAUUAAAUAAAUUAUGGCAUAUUUAUAUAAUGGAAUAUAAGUCUACACCAAAAAUAUGAUAUGUUGAUAUGUACAAAUAUUAUAUUAAAUAGUAGCAUGUAAAAGAUGCAGUGUGUGAAAUAGAAGAUUAAGAAGUUUAUUUAACAGUAUGCAAAAUUUGAUCUUUUCUUGUAAAAACCAAAUUUAUAUCAAAUGUUAAUAACAUUGCAAAGUAGGAGUUUUUUAUUCUUUCUGCUUUUCUAAUUAAAACACAAUAAAAGUGAAUUAAAGAAUCAGAAAUAAAACAAUGCAUUUACUUUUUUGAAGUUUUGCUACUAGGCUUUUACAAUUUUUUAAAAAACAAGAUACCUUGACAAGGAGAGAGAGAAGAAUUCUAGGCUGUGAAAAUUUAUGUAGAUAUUGAGGAACAGUGAAGGUACAUGGAGUCAGCCCUUAUAAUUCUUAUCAUGUAGCACAGUACUUCUCAAACUGUAGCCUGUGGCAGGAUCACCUGGAGGCUGGGCCCCACCCCCUACCCUAGACUUUCUGAUUCAGUAGGUCUGGGUGGAACCAAAGAAUUUUCAUUUCCAGUAAGUUCUCCAGAUAUUGCCAAUGCUGCUUACUAAGGAACCCCACUUUGAGAACCACUGCCAUAGAAACUUACCAUGGCUUUGCCAUUUGCCUCGGUUAUAAAACUAUUGAUGCUUGGAAUUCAAUCCUAGGGAUUAUUUCAAAGCCCACACUCUUUCAACAAUGUUUUCGGUCUUAGCUAGGUAUUAGAAUCCUAUGGAGUAUUUUUUUAAAAUCCUGUUGCCUGAUGUCCGCCCCAGAACAAUUAACUGAAACCUCUGGAAGGUGGGCGGAGGGUGGGUAGACGGGCGGGAAUGAAAGGAUUCCAAAUGCUUCUAGCAGCCAAUCAUGGUUGAAAACUUUUGUCCACCAAAACCCUUUCAAGCUACUAUUCUAAUAUUUAUUUCAGAAAUUAAAAAGCUGUACUAAUUUCAGAAAUUAAAAAACUGAAGUCCUCUUCUUAAGUUAACUGAACUAUAAAUGCUUUGAUGAUUCUCAGUAACCAAGCAGAUAGUUUAGUAAAAUGAUUCUCCAUUGACAUGCUUAAUAUGUCCCUGGAAAGCACGUUUAUAAAAAUUUCUCUAUUUAAAUAUCUUGUCUUCUGCUGGGUUGGAACAGAGAAUUUUCCUCUGAGAACCUUUUGUGGUGAAAUAAGUAAAGGUUUUCAGUAGAUCAUAUAUACCUUGGUAUUCAUUUUUUCUUUUAGAAAGAAACCAAAUUCAAUAAAUAGAUGGCCAUAAAAAGUACUGAUUAACAUAAUUACCCAUAAUCAUGUUACACCAGAUAUAGUACACAGACAAUUGUAUAGUACUAUUGCUGUCCUUGGAAUUGCUCAGGACUAACCUGAUAUUCAUGUCUGCUUCACAUAUAAGGCAUUAGUCUGACACAUAAAUGAACAGUGGCGCUCAACAUCACAUGUAUGUCAAGAAUGAGUGUUGAAGGGCAUUGAAUAAGUUGCCACCUUCUGAACAAGUUGUGUUUCAAAUUUGCAUUGUAGAUUAAUUCUUGGGAAUGCAGAGUUUACUUGUCUAUGGAAAUAAUAGUUGUGCUUUCCACUUUAAAAAAAAAAAAUCUCAGUGCUGGGAGACUGGGAGCCAGGAGAAACUGACAGCAGAGUAGGGUUUUCUCACCAAUUCUCCCUUUCUUUACCUCAGAAGUGUUCUCUCAUCCUUCCCCAUCUACUUCAGUUAUCUAUUGUUAUAUAACAAACCAUCCCAAAACUUAGUGGCUUCAGAUAAUGAUGAUUUAUUACUUCUUACAAUUCUAUGGGUCAGGACUUCAGGUAGGAUUGGCCAGGCAGGUUUUGCUUCAUUGGUCAUUGAUUGGGGGUCACCGACUCAGGCUUAUUCUGCUGGUGGCUGGGCUGUGAUAGAAGCCCCAAGAAGGACUUACUUAGUUAUAUGGUGAGCUGGUGCUUCUCAUGUGGCCCACUGCGUAGCUAGUUUUGGCUUUCUCACAGCUUGGUGGUUUUAGGUUAGUCAGCCCUUUACACAGAAGCUGGCUUCAAAAAGGAAACUUCCAGUCCUCUCUCAAGCCUGGGGAUAAGAAGUCCCAAGAUCCAGAACAUCACUUCCUCCACAUUCUGUUGGUCAAAGUUACAUGGCUACCCUAGAUUUAAAAGGGAGGAGAAAUAGACCCCUCUUUUCAAGAGGGGGUGGCAUGUGCAUAUAGGGAAGGAAAAAAUUGAUGGUGGCCAUCUUUGGAGAUUAUUUUCUAUGUCACCCCUUCAUUGUUGGAUUCUGGAGGAGGUUGAUGUAAGGCCUGAACUUUCCAGAGUAGAACCACCAAUAUGGUCAUGUCCCCACAAGUAAGUUCAGCAGAGGCCAGGGAGGUGAAGAAUCUUCAGCAGCAGCUGAAAAAAGUGAAUGCACAUUCGCCACGCACAUCUGUCUUUUAGCUCCCAUUUUGCCAGAAAUGGAAAUCUAAGCUUUCAUCUGAGGAGGAAAUUGAGGAGAGUGGCUGUAUCAGGAUUAGACUUAGCUGGGAAUAUCAGAAAUCCAAAAUAAAGGGAAGUAAAAGGGAGUUUAUUUUCCUCAUGUAAAGUUCAGAGGCAGGCAGUGCAGGGCUGACAUGGCUUUUUCCACUCACCUCCACCUCCAAAACAGGGUUGGAAAAUGACAACUCUCCCAUAAUUAUUGCACCAAUGAAAUACAUGUCCCAAGUCCAGAUGACCACAAUUCCUUCUUAGUGGGUCUUUUACUCUGGGAGAUUAUCCAUCCAGGAUACUAAGUUUCUCAAAUGACCACUUUUAAUGGAAACUGUGAUAACAUAGCACAGGCUUUGUGAACAAUUAGAUAGAAUCUCAAACUUUAACAUUUUUCCCAAGCUCCUCAAGCCUAUUUAAAUGUAAAAUGAGUUAUUUACUACUUUGUCCAAUUUCCCUUUGUUUUUGAAAACUACAUGAAAUUAUUUGUAUAGUCAUUGUUGGUUGAAGUAGUAAAGCAAUUAUGCACAGGAAUAGAUGAGACAGACACAUAAAUGCUACUUUAACCACAUUCUUGUUGAUGGGGAAAAAGGAACACUAGACUAGGAAUCAGAUUAGCAUGCGCCUUGGAGCAAAUCACUAAAUGUCUUGGAAACUUCAUCUCUUCACCUGUAAAAUGGAGAUGAUAACGUAAUCUGCAGACAGGGUGCUUUAGAGGAAGGGAUCAUUAAAUGAGAUGAUGAUGCAAAUAUAUUAGAAAACAAAUUGCCACUACAAGCUACAGAUAUUUUACUUCCAUUAAUUUCAUUAAUAGCAUCAUCAUCAUUUUAUGUUGUAAUAAAGGCAAUUCACUAUGCUUAGUUCUGAAGUGUCCAUGCAUUAAAAUAAUCAAUGAUGGAGAUUCUGUCCAUUUUGCAUGCUUUUCUCUCUGGGCAUGGGUGCCUUGGCAGGGUCCUGGGUGGCACGUCCUGUGGAAACUGUCAUACAUACAACCUAUUGGAUUAGUAAAGCCUGAAGACUUGGGAGAUGUAUAAGGGAAAGAAAGACAAGAAAGACACUAUAAUGACAGCCAACACAUAAGUCCUCAGUGCUAGGGCCCUGGGUUAGUACUUUUUCCUGCUUUAAUCUCUUUUCACCUACACCAGAGCCCUAUGAAGAAAGUGUUAUUAUUAGACUCCUACAAGCCUUAAAGAGGUUUUUUUUUUUUAAUGUGACUUUUAUUUUAGGUUCAGGGGUACAUGUGCAGGUUUAUUACAUAGGUAAACUUCUGCCACGGGGGUUUGUUGUAAAGAUUAUUUCAUCACCCAGGUAGUAAGCCUAGUACCCAUUAGUUAUUUUUCCUGAUCCUCUCCAUCCUCCCACCCUACACCCUCCAAUAGGCCCACUGUCUAUUGUUCCCCUCUAUGUGUCCACAUGCUCUCAUCAUUUAGCUCCCACUUAUAAGUCAGACAUCAAGUAUUUGAUUUUCCAUUCCUGCCUUAGUUUGCUAAGGAUAAUAGCCUCCAGCUCCAUCCAUCUUCCUGCAAAAGAUAUGACCUCAUUCUUUUUUAUGGCUGCAUAGUAUUCCAUGGUGUAUAUGUACCACGUUUUCUUUUUCCAGUCUAUGAUUGAUGGGCAUUUAGGUUGAUUUCAUGUCUUUGCUAUUGUGAAUAGUGCUGCAAUGAACAUACAUGUGCAUGUGUCUUUAUGACAGAAUGAUUUAUAUUCCUUCUGGUAUAUACCUAGUGAUAGAAUUGCUGAGUUGAGUGGUAUUUCUGUUUUUAGGUCUUUGGGAAAUCACCACAAUUUCUUCCACAAUGGUUGUAGUAAUUUACAUUCCCACCGACAGUGCAUGUGUUCCUUUUACUCUGCAACCUUGCCAGCAUCAGUUAUUUUUUGACUUUUUAAUAAUAGCCAUUCUGACAGGUGUGAGAUGGUGUCUCAUUGUGGUUUCGUUUUGAAUUUCUCUAAUGAUCAGUGAUGUUGAGCUUUUUUUCAUAUGCUUGUUGGCCAUAUGUAUGUCUCCUUUUGAAAAAUGUCUGUUCAUGUCCUUUGCUCACUUUUUAAAGAGGUUUCUGAGGUGUGGAAGUUUCAUAGAAAGUAGAAUAGCUGAGGUUGAAUCUAACACACUUCUCACCCUGUGCUGCUACUUCAAGUGCUCACCAUGAACUUCAGCACUGACUAAACAAAGCCACAGAGAAGAUUAGAGAGCAUUCAUUCCAGAGAUAAUCCCACCGCCAGGGCUGGACUACGUGGACAUGUGUCCUGGGUAGUUCUUCAAAAGGGCCCCAUGCUGAGUUGACUGCUCUGCUGGUUCCAUCUUGAAGUCCUUAAUUGCUUCUGAGCAAAUGGCCCCAUAUUUUUGUUUUUCACUGGACCUCACAAAUAUUGCUGGUCCUGGGAGACACUGAGGUAACAUGUGUAAGAGAAAAAGAAAGAAGGAGCUAACAUUUGCUAAGCACUAUGACAUGCCAGGCAUAAAUUUAUGUCAUUUUUAUACCCAUUAACUAAUUUCACUUCUAGGAAAACUCUGCAAGAUAAAUAAGUUCAUCGCUUUAUAGAUAAACAGGUUCUCAGAGAGGCCAAGUAACUUGCAUCGGUUACACAGCUGGGAAGAGGUGGAGCCUCGAUUCAGGGCCUUCAGUGCUCUUAUUCUUUUAACCCCUCCAGACUGUGCCAUGGUUGAGAUAAUAAAUACCUACUCUUCCUGGGGGUAUUAUAAUGAGGCAAUUUUCUACCUCUGCAGAAAUACAUUAAAUAUUAUUAAAGGCAUAUAGUUUACAAUAAUGUAGAGUUGCUGUCUGCAAAACUUAUUUCUGGUUGAGACAGACCUAAUGAAAGAUUCUCAAAGAUAGAAGAUGUGAUAUAUAAAUAUGACCAAGUUAUUUCAGAAUUACUGGACAAAGGACUAUGCAAUGUUAUUUUUAUAAGCUAAUUGCAGAUUGCAUCAAGGUUCUUAAAUCUCUGCAGAGCAAUGAACUCGGAGUCCAGAGAACUGAAUUCUAUUUUUAACUUUAGAUAACCUUGGCUAAGUCAUUUGGCUUCUCUGAGUCUCAAAUAGGAAUCAAAAGGGGAAGAUCCAAAGCCAUAGUAAAAAGGUUUUUAUCAUAAAUGAACCCUAAAUAGAAUUUUUUAAUGCCCAGGGCAGGAAGCCUAGAUUGGCUUUCCAUCUGGAGAGAGGUCCUUAAGUAAGAGGAAGGAUAGGAAUGAGAAUAGAGGAGGGAUCUUUUAUCUCAAUACCCUGAAAGUUCUUUGCUUGGCCAAUUUUCUCACCUGUCCAUGGGCCUUUAGCUGUCUGCCUCCAGUAGCUAGGGUCGCUGACCUGGGAUAGCAUUGAGCCUGCCACCAAGCUGCAGAGAUAGUACAGGGUACUCAGUGAGAAGGGAGGAAAGGAGAAAGCUCUAAAUUUUGCCAAUAUUCCCAAUAUUUCUCAAUUUCUUUUGCUUUCUUUUUAUCUCGAUGCCCUAUGGGCAAAGACCCAGUGGCCAUGUCCUAGCUAUUGCUCUAAGAUUGAUUAGGAGUGGUUUCACAGUCAUGGGUCUAUGCUGAGCUGACAAGAAUGCCCAUGAUUUAUUAGUGAUGUCUGUCAUGGGCACUGCAGGUAUGGGGGGUGAUAGAUGUGCCUCAUAUCUCGUCUAUUAGAUAUUCACCAUUCCUAGAUUAAGGUAGUCUUUCCAGAAAUAUUUGUGGGAUGACUGAACAGCCAUUACUGUAAGUGUUAAAUUUGUUGUACCUAUGAGGAAAAAAAUGUAGUCCCAAAAGUUAGCUAAGAAGUUUCCAGCUAAUUGAGGGCAUUGCCCUAUGUACAUGAAAAACAUUUAUAUUUCUGUUGAUUUCUUAGCAUGUGGAUCACAGAAUAUUUGUAUUAGAAUUACAUAAUAAGCUCUGUUAAACUACAGAUUCCUGGGCCUCACCCUACUUAUUUACAACAUCUUUGGAGGGUAAGGCCUAGGAAUCUGCAUUUUCACAAAUGUCCUUAGUGAUUGGGGAUGAAGGUGUGCAUGUGAAGUGGGAGAACCAUUGCUUUAUAAGACUGGGUAAGAAAAAUUAUAUUUUUUAAAUCGGCAAUAUUUUCAUUUACCAUAUCAUAAUCUAAACUAGGAAUGAGCACCAGUUUUCAAAUGGUGUUGGAAUUCAGUAGGGGUUUGUAAAAUACAAAUAGUUUGAUUAAAUAAAUUCUUCAGUGUUAAGUGGGGGUGGAGGUCUACAUAAACAAAACUUGGGACCUAGAUAAACCAAGCUUAAGGACAAAAAAAAAAAGUCUUUUAAAAGUCUUAUGGUCAUAGCUUAUUCAACCAAGUAACACUAGGCAAGGUUACAGAAAUACAGGUUUUUUUUUUUUUAAUCCCUAUACCCUUGACAUGUGAAUGUGCACAUGAAUGUGCAAACCAUGAAAGGGGAACAGGGUUGCAGACUGCUAUAACAAGAGCUGAAAGGUUGAAAGGUAGAAUCGACUUUAAGCAAGGGUCAUCUUCUGGGAGAUAAUUAAACAACACUAAGUUGAUAUGGGAGGAGGAGGGAAGGAAAAAAGAUUAUGAGAAGUAUUUAGAAGGCCUUAGAAGAGGUACUCCAACUCAAACAAAUAGUCACAUGAGAGAAGGACAGUAUUGUUGAAAGCACAUAGGCUUUUGGCCUGGCAACCUGGGUUUGAAUGUGACUCUGCCACUUGACUAGUCCUCUGACUGAUUACAGGUAAUGACUGAAUUACUUAAUUCCUCUAAAUCCCCGUUUCCUCAUUUGUGAAUCUGGAUAAGGAUAGAACUUACUCAACCAGUGGCACAAGUGGUGAUGAGAAUUAAGAAGGAAAACAAAUAUAAAGUGCUGGCAUGCGACAAGCUCUCAAUGACAUUUGUGGGAGAGAAGUCAAAGCUAGAAUGACUUUCUCUUUUGAAGUAUAGCUAAUCAAUAUAGUUAUUCCAAUGUGGAAUCAUUUUCUUAUGAGAGCGUGUGCGAAGUUCACCAAGGCUCAGUUGCUUAUACCUGAGGAAUGCCUUAUUAACCCUAGACUUACUAAUACGCUAACAUUAUAUCAGUGAUGAUGAGAUAUCAUUAGAGAAGGCACAUUCCAAGGUCAUCAUACAUCAAUCGUCCUAAAAGGUCCUUGAUAAAGAAAUAACUAAAUCCCUAGUGACAUAUCUUGCAAACACAGUAGUUGGAAACUGUUUCCUAAGUUUCUUAUCUUCAAUGAUAUUUUAAAAUUAAGAAGUCAAAGACUUAAGUACUGUUUGUGGGAGUUCUGGAAUUAGAAGCCCAGACAGGAACAGUGUAUUGUGGCACUGACAGCCUGGCCUUUCUUAUUUAUUUUACAUUAUUAGCGUGUUCUCUCAAGCCUACUUGCAUAAAUACACAAUUAUAUGUAUUUAAUGAAUUCACUCUUAAACAGCUGUAGAAAAUGUGCUUUACUAAUAGGGGGGCAUCCAGUCAGAUAAAGCAGUCAUAACGCGUUGCGCGUGUGUGUGUGUGUGUGUGUGUGUGUGUGUGUGUGUGUGUGUGUUGGUUUAAAAUUUCAUGAGUCAAUGGAGGAUAAAUAUGCAUAAAUGAAAUAUAUAUUUAAAAGCUGCCUUUUGAGCCUGUAAAAGCUACUUUUCUUUCUGACACAAAAGAAAUAUCUGCUUUCUUAUAUAAAGAGAAUUAUUGGACAAAUUGAGUCCAUGUUCACAAACAUUAACGUCUAAAGCAAAGCAGUUAGAAAUAAACUCUAUCUAGUCUAUUGAGUCUCAAAAUUCAGCCCAUUAUCCAACUGGGGAGCUUUUUACAGUGCAGAUUCCUGGGCUCACCUUAGGAGAUUGAUUCUGUGAGUCUGGAGCAGGGCCUAGAAAUCUGCAUUUUUAGCAGCCCAAAGUGACUCUGAUCCAAGUGCUCUAAGUAUCAGAAUUUCAGAAACUGCAUUUUAUCCCUUCUAGCCUGAAAGGUUCAUUCAGGGAUAGAACGAGGUUAAUAGGUUGCUCGAUUAAUACAGAAUUGGAGCAGAGGAAUAGACUGUUCUGAAGGGAGAAUCCUAUAUGAAACCAAAAGCAGCACCUAUUAAACAACUGGAUUAGUCUUUUAUAAAUAGAGCGCUUUAUGCAUUGGACAGACUCCAAGGAAAGCAAACAGAUUCUUGCCCUUGUUCCUCCUUUUUAAUCCCCUUUACUGUUCAUUAGUACUUCAUCCUACAAGUACAGUUCCUGAAAAGCAGCUCCCAGUGAAGUUUAGGAGUCACUUGGAGCCCUUGAAGAUAUCUUCAUCCCAUCAGCGAGCCAUUUACACAUAUUGCCCUGGAGAACGCUUCUACUGGCUACUGUAUUCUAUUCUGUGUGCCUUCCUGAUAGCGGAUACUGGCUACUCUGGAUUCAAGUAUCUCUUCUUCUAAACUUGUAUCCCUGUGUCUUUUGUUGUAUCUACUCCUUACAGGUCCUUGACUCCAUAUGAAAGCACUUAGGGGAAAAAAAAUUAAAAGUACGUUUAUAUAAGGCAGUAUUAUUAACAUACUUUUUAUUUGCCUCAAGGUCAUUGACGUGAAAUUUCACAAUUGCACUCUUGAAUAUACAACAUAAUUAUAUUAUGUAACAACUCUUCUGAAAUAGUUUGGAUUUCAAAUUUCCAUUCCAUGAGCACCAUGAAUACAUAUUCAUACUUGUUGGAUCAUGAGUCUAGAUUAGUGGUUCAGAAACUAAAGUCAUUAAGCAUUAACUGGGUCCGUCAUACAAAAUCCAAUAGAGUUCACUUAUUAAGUAUCAACUGAGUCUGUCUGGAUCUGUAUCAACUCAGUAAGUUCACUAAGUUAGGAUACUAGCCAUUCAGUAUUUCCAUAGCAAAAAGGCACAAGAUACUUGAAUAAUGUUUGAACUCUAUAAUUCUACUACCAUUGUUCCAGACUGCUGGAAUCCCUUAAUUUGAAAUAAAUAAUUAUUUUUAUGGUUCUUUGAGAAUGGCAGUCCUUUAAUACCUUAUAGUUUGGAUUUCUUGAAAUAUUUUUUUUCUCAACUACAUGUGCCGUUGAAUUCAUUAAAAAAUUGUUCAGUAACAGUCCUUAACAAAAGUAGCUUCUGUGGUGUUGACAACCAUGCCUUUUCCUUUGAAAUAAAAACAAGUAUUUAUCCAAAACUAGGCAGAAACAGUUAACUUGAUUAGAGAGCACUAAAUUUAUUGUAGAGUCAAUCCUGCAAAAUCAAAAGGGGAUAGAUUCCUUAUGGACUCUUGCCUGAUAAGAUUUUUACCCUGUUUGCAAGCUAACAAAUUAGCUUAUCUCAUUUCAUAAAUGAUGGCAGAAAGAAUGAUAUUCUUGGAUCAGAUAUGAAGGAGAGUUUGUUAGUCACAGCAAUAGCAGUAGCUGGAGUAUCAGCAUUUUCCUAUGCCUGUUCCCUGAGUCCCAAUUCCCACAAGGUAAUGCACAGAGAUCCAGGGAACACCUGUACAUGCAGCAAGUUGCAUUACUGGAAGGGACCCUGAGCUUACCAAACCUGAAUCUUUUAUAAUGGGAUGUUUAAGUAUGCCUUGCCUUUGAUGCAGCAAGAGACUGUCUCUACCCUUCAAGUUUCUUCAGUAUACAUUUUUGGAAAGCUACUCUGGAACAAAGGCAGUCAGAACCUCUAUUCACAAGAUGUGCAGAAACUUGAAAGACCGGUGGAAACUUGCCCACCAAAAAUGCCAUGGAAAAUACUGUGUUUUUGAACACAUUAACUUGAGCCUUUUAGAGAUGAGUUUCAGCUAAUGCCGUUUCAUUUUAGACAUUUUAUUUAUUAGAAAAUAGACAGAUUUUCUAGGAAAUCACUUUUUCUACCAGAAUGGGUACCAUUUGUUAAGGUUACUAAUAAUACAGUAUUCAUGCAAAUAUUUGUUUUUCUUUAUUUUCCUCCUAAUAUAAUGCAUCUCUCUCCAGAAUACAGCUGAAGAGAUGUUUUAUAUUUUACCCCUUUAAGUGAUCAUUUAGUAUAGGAAUUACGUGGCUGUUGCAGAUUUCGGUAUUCUAAAAGACAAAAUUCAAAACUGAAUUCUCUGGGAACAUUGAAGCAUAUCCUGAAGCGGCAAUAUUUUUGUUUGUAUAUUUUUAAAAAUAUCUUGUAAUUUGGCUAUGUCCGGAUGGCUAAGGAAAAUAUUUUACUUAACUUUUUUUUUGGCCUGAAUUAUCACACAAGUGUUUAAGCAUAUUUUCCCUUGAUUGUAUUGUAGAGCUUUUAACACAUAGAUAUGUUCUGUUUAUUUAACAUGCCUGGAAGGACUCAGGAAGGAGAACCAAUAAAUACGUUCUUACCAUUAACUUUGGGCUUCUGCCGAAUUGACUUUGUCAAGUAAAUUUGACAUGCUUAACACUGGGAGUGAUUAUUUACCAUCUUCUGAAUUAAUAUAAAGAAUUCACAGUCAGAUUUUUGUUCUUGCAAACAGACUUUUCUCUUUAAAAAGAUGUGUUUUCAUGGCUGCAUAUUAUGUUUCAGUUAUGCAAUGUCUUUCCUGAAUUCCCUCUUUGCACCAGUGCCAUUGCUAUUAGGGUGAAGUUGAUGGAAUGCACUGUUUCCAUUUGCUUAUACAAGUGAAUUGCUACUCUCUAUAUAUCUAUUUGAAACAUAACUGAAAAUGCAAAUAUACUAUGGAGGUCCAAUUUUUAAAAUAUGGAGUCACGCUCAAUUAACAGUAACAAACUUGUGUGAUCUUUAUCUUUCCUGUUUUGUAGAAUUAAUAGGUAAUUGGUUUUCUGUCCUUGCGAUAGUUUGCUCAGAAUGAUGGUUUCCAGCUUCAUCCAUCCUUCAUACAAAGGAUAUGAACUCAUCCUUUUUUAUGGCUGCAUACUAUUCCAUGGGGUAUGUUCUCACUCAUAGGUGGGAAUUGAACAACGAGAACACUUGGACACAGGGUGGGGAACAUCACACACUGGGGCCUGUCGUGGGGUCGGGGAUGGGGGAGGGAUAGCAUUAGGAGGUAUACCUAAUGUAAAUGAUGAGUUAAUGGGUGCAGCACACCAACAUGGCACAUGUAUACAUAUGUAACAAACCUGCACGUUGUGUACACGUACCCUAGAACUUAAAGUAUCAUAAAAAAAAUCAGAGAUGAAAAAGAAAAAAAAAGUUAAUAGGUCAAUGUUUUUAAUUUCAAUUGUGAAUAUUAAGACUGUUAUUGAGUGGCAUUUGGAUUUCUUUAUUUUUCUAAAUAUAUGUGGCAAAUGCUGCUGCCAAUACUUAAAUAUAAACAUAUUCUCCCUUUUUUUAAUCCCCAAAGAAUUUACCAUAUAGAAUUCUUUGAAGAGGAUUAGAAUGUGGACAUAUUUUUGGGGAGACCACCCUUCAGCCCACUACACCUAUCCUGAGCAACUUUUUAACCUCAUAUUGUAACACAAGAAUGUUUUCAUUUUAUUAAAAUUCUUUGCAAAUAUCUUUUCAAAUGGUCCUUAACAUUUGCUGGAUGCAUCACAAUGAUCACUUCAACUAUUGUUGAACAUAAGAAAUUGACUAUUUAAAAUAAUAUUGCAGUAAACAUUUUUGUGUAUAAAGCUGUUCUUCCAUAUUUUGAGAUUGUUUCCUCCUUAAUUUUUAGAAGUGAGUUCAGUGGGCCAGAGGGUUGUACCAACUUACAAUCCACCUAUAAUGUAAGAAAGCCUCUUUAACUGCUCCUUUGUAUUUAAAGUUUUUUUUGGUAAAUUGAUAAGUGGAAAAUGGUAUAUUAUUUAAAUUUGUAUUUCCUAGAGCAUUAAUACAAUUAGAUUUUUUUCUCACAUAUUUUAAAUGGAAUAUUAUUCAUUUUUAAAAUUUUCUGUGUCCUCUGACCAAUUAUCUAUUGGCUAAUGCUUUUUAAAAAUAUCUUAAUAAUCUUGUAUGAACUUUAAAUUGUAAAAAUAGUGACUUUUAAAUUUGUGCCGUAAAUGUUUUUCUGAGUUGGUGGUUUGCUCUUGAAUUUGAUAAUUUGUGAUAAUUUGAUAAUUUGGAGUUUGGACAAAUGUAAAUAUCCCUUUUCAUUUAUGUUGGGAUGCUUUACUGAGGUUUUCCUUUGUAUUUCUCCCACUUGACACAGUAGGAGAAUAUGAGAAAAUCUUCCUAUAUUUGGAGAGCCAGUGCAUUUAAUUUUCUCCUAGCUUUGUUUGGUAACUCUUUAAUCCAUCUGUACUUUUAUUUUGAUACAUGAAGAGAAGUGAGAUAACUUUUUCCAAACUUUUCCCAAGCUCCUAAACAGUUAUCUCAAAAUCAUUAUUAUUGAGUAAUCCAUCUCUUUACUGUUGAUUUGUGAUGACUUCUUUGUAAUUUUUUAAAGCUUCUCAUAUAAACUGGGGUUUAUUUGGAAGACAUGUAUUUUAUCACAUCUAUCUAUUUUUGGCCAAUAUGAGAGACUAAAAUUAUUGAAAUUUUAAGCUAUGUUUUAAUAUAUAAGCAAAUCAGGUCAUGAAGUUCUCAUUUGUCUCUAAAUCAGAUAAGACUUUUGUUUAAAUAAAAUGCUGUCAUCCAUGUUAUAAAAGCAAAUUAGCUAGCAUAUGGAUUAUCUUGCCAAUAAUUAAUAUCAGCCUUUAUUGCUAUAAAUUAGCACUAAUAUUUUUUAAUAACUCAUAAUGGAGUACUCUGUACAUGUCAUGUUUAUAUCUUUCCCUCUCCUGCACCUAUCCUAUCUCCAAAUUCAUUGCUAAAUAAUAUACUGUAUUUAGAAACGUCCUGAAAACUUGAUUUGACACAAACUCUUUCAGGGUGCUGAUUUCUUUCUCCCUCAGCCACAGUAAUGACCCGAUGCUACUCAGCUGAUCAGAUCCCUGCAUUCUGAUUUGGUUAUUUAGAUCAGGGUUUCUCAACCUUGGCACUGUUGAUAUAUGGGGUUAAAUAAUUCUCUGUUGUAUCCUACACAUUGUAGGAUGCUUAGUAACAUCCCCCACUAGUUUCCAGUAGCACCAUCCUCUUUCUCCAUCCCCAUCCCCACCCCUAGUGUGACAACCAAAAAAUGUUCCCAGGUAUUGCCAAAUGUCUCUUGUGGGACAAAACUGUCCCCACUGAGAGUUAUUGAUUCAGAUAAAAGUAGUCAGGCAGCAUGUAGCGUAAUAAAUUUAACUUUUAUUCAUUUAUUAUUAUUAUUUAUAAUAUUAGUAAUACAAUCAGGGUAGAUCUCGAGCCUUCCAAUUAAUUGCACAAUGGUCCACUAUCAUUGGGCUCACAAAAAUUAACCCCAGGGCAUUCUGCUUUGCCAUGUGAUUUAAAUAUGACCAUAGUAAGAACAGUGACAUUAUGAUUGCUCAAAGUAAAACAUCUCAGAGAUCUCUUUUGGCUCACCUGUCCCUACUUAACCUAUGUUGAUGGUAAAUUUGAAAAGUUGUCGAUUUGAUAACCAUAUUGGUACAUGCAAAUGAAUUAUGCCCUGAAUUUUAAUCUAAUAUUUUUUGAUAUUGAGAAAAUGGCCCAAAUUUUAAGACCGUCAUUCUAUGAAUCAUCUUGCCUUUGACUUUAGCAUAUAACCAUGGCUGUCUGAGCCAGUUAGCUCAGAGGGGUUUUACAAGAUGAUAAUGAGGCCAAUGUUGCAGUUUCAAUUAGCUUCACAGAAGAAAAAGCCAGCUUCACAGCAGCAGACUGCACUGCUAACCCCAGCCACCACACUCAGCCAAUGGUCAAAAGAAAGAGGAGAACAGAGAAUGUUGCCGACUCAGCACUCCCAGGACCAUUUAGCCUGGACAAGUAAAGGUCAUAUCUCUUUGAUGAUGAUGAACCAUCCGCAUUAUAUUCCUACACCAAUUCACUGCAGAAACACAUAAUGAAGAGUACUCUCUAAAUCAGAGCUCCCUUUAUAGCCAACAUAGAUCAUUCAGGCAAAGACUUUUUUGUUAAAAAUUUUGUUGUGAAUUAACAAAUAGGAUAGCUGCAGUUUUAGAAGGUAUUUAAAUAACUUUUACUUUGCUUUUGAAUUUGCAGUAUUAACCAUGCAUUUGAAGUAAGUACAUUUUGUCCACUCAUGAAAUUAUUUCCUAAUAGUUCACUUAAAGGAAUGGGUCAAAUGAGCAUAAAUUUGCCUGCCAUUAUGUAAAUAUAAUGGCUCAUCAGGUAAUUUUCUUCAUUGAAAUGGGAAGACUUGUAUAAGUGUUGAAAUGGAGACUGAAUUUUACUUGCAUUUAAAAUUUGUUUUUUAUUGUCAAAGGGGUAUUUACAGGGAUCCCUGGGACAAAUUUUCCUAAUAUUAAUGUAUGUGUUAUACAAAAUGUAGCCACCUUGGAAAUACGGCUCUCUGCAUCUAUUUUUUAUUCCAAAGAUUGUACUCAAUUCUGCUUUUGGAAUAUUUGCAUUUUUGCUGCUGACCUACUGCAUGGAAUUCAAUGGAGACCCAUGAAACUAGGCCAAUUUGGUUUAUAGUCUCAAUUUCAGAAUGAAGACACAUUUGCUUCUUUCUAUUUACCCCUGGUCUUUGAAUUUUGAUCAUACUCAUCCAAUCCCAAGCCACAUUUUCCCAGUAGGGAGCUUCUGGAGGUUAAUAUUAUUUUUCUAAUGAUUUUCCUUUCUCACUGCUUUCUAAAUUUUUCUUCUGGCUUAUCAAGAAAGGCAUAGGAAUUUUACCAGCAGUGUUGGUAGUAUAUUCUGGUAAUGAAUAGAUAUUCAGUUUCAGGCUCUUCUAUUCAAAAUGUAUUCAUCAAAAUGCAAUCAACUUUCAUAGCCUAUGGAGAAAAUAGCUUUUAGAAAUUGGCAUUUACCUCACCUCAUCAAAGGUCUGCUUAACACAUUGAAAUAAUCUGAAUGAAUAGCAAUAGGUAAACCAGACAGAUUGAGCCUUGAAUGCAGGAAUGUCUACAGAUAUUUCCAUGGACUGUUUCUUACCCAGUGAGUUCAGGAACAUAUGGAAUCCUGGCUUUCAGGGGUAUUUUUUACAUUAUUUUCUACAGUUGUAGCUGCAUGGGUACCACAUUUUCCCAACUGCUUGUUUGUUAGUAUUGUGUUCAGAAUCUCUUGUUUCAAAAUGCAUGAUGUUCUCCUCUUUUUAAAAAUCCUAAUAUUUUUCAAGUGUUUCUGUGUGUCAGGCACUGUGCUAAGCACUUUCAUGGAUUAGUUCAUUUAAUUCAUUUAAUUUUACAGUGGCCAUAUGGCAUACACUAGCUACUGUAAUUCUCCUUGUACAGCUAAGGAAACUGAGGGGUAGAAGUUAGUCAGAGGCCCAGGAUAAUACAGCUGAUACUAACACAUGACAGAGCCAGAAUGUGACUUAGUUCUGUAUGAAUCCAGAGCCCAUAUUCUUAACUGCUAUGCUAUAUUGCCUCCCAGAAGUCAUUAUCACAAAGGGUUUGCAUUAUUUUUUAUUUCCAAUAAUAACAUAAUUUUAUUUGUUCAUCAUACUUGAUUUAAAACAAAUAAAAAUGAUACCCAAAUAUCUUUCAUAUCAACCAAACCAAGACUCCUAUAGAGUGGAGCCUGUCUGUGCAAAUUUAACUUACAGUGGGGCCUUUAUCUUUAGUUUUCAUGCGUUUAAAUCUGUAGUCAGGGAUUGGUUCAUGUUUUGAGUCAUCGUAUUUCACUCCCUAUGACAUUUCGGGUACCUAAAACAUGUUCACUGAUGUUUUGAAGAAUGGAAUUUCCACCACUUCCUUUAGAAGACUAUAAAUAAAAAAUGAUAGAAAGUGUCAAACUGUAAUUACAUUGAGGGUUUUAGUAACCUCAUAAACCAUAAGAAUGAAAUACCAAAAAAAUUUUUUUCAACUGCCACCAUCAAAAUCUCAUUUGCUGAUUCCAUUUUUGCAGCAUUGAUGGAAGUAAUCCAGUUAGGCUGACAUUUUUAUAGAGUAUAGUUUAAUGUUCAAAUAAGCCCUGUGUUAUUUCACCAUUUUUAUUUUUUUAUGGAAAGGAUUUUUUUUCUUCUGUAAUGAUUUGAACUGUGUUAUAAAGUAAAUGAAAAUGUGUCUUGUUGGUUGGAUUGUGACUCCAGCAGACACAUUUUAGUUGAUGUAAAGGUCUUUGCCAUAAUCACAGUUGAUGUUUACAAAUACACACCUCCUUUAAUUUUUAAUGCUGAUUGUAUUUCUUAAUGCAUCUAAUCACAGAAAAUCUGUCAAAAAGGAAAGCUUUGGUCUCAAACAUAUGCUUGGGUUUCUGUUAGCAGGAAACAAAUGUCCAAAUAUGAUUGCAUACCAGCUCACACACAUGCUCAUGCACGUGCUCACACUUGUACUCAAGUAUGGAUCCAAGUGUGAACCUGGUGACAUAGUGGCACUUAGAGCCAAAUACUAAACAUAUGUCGAAAUUUGGUGUGAUCACAACAGCAGAAUGGUACAAUAUUGUUUCAUUCAUUCUGAUGCAGGAAGAGAAGCCAAAUGACAGCAAAUCAUGAAACAAAUGUUACUCCCUUCUCAGAGCGUUAUGUCUGAAUAAUUGAGUGAAAAAUAAGACCAAUUUGUUUCAGUCUGAUUUUCUUGUCAUUGGUAAAUUGAUGGAUAUAUUUCUAUUCACUUCUAAGAGAAAAUAAGCUGACAAACCUUUAAUGGUUGAGACAUGUUAGAUAAAACUGCUGGUAUUUGAUGGUUUCUGCCCUAUAGAUCAAAAUAUGUCUAUCAUUCAUCAAAAAAUAGUAUUAGCAAAUUCAGUUGUUCAAUCUGACAGAAUGUUUAUUGUAUUCAUUUUCUCCUUUUAAUAUUUAUUUCUAGCUGUACUUUUUAAAAGAUGGCAUACUUUUUAAUCAUAUGAAAAGGCAUAACUUUAAAGAUGGACCUCAUUCAUACGAAUAACUUGUUUAUGAGUCAAAUAUUUUCGAUAUAUUUUAUCCAUGAAUUCCCUCAUGAGUGCUCAAGAUAGAGCAGUUGAUCGUCACUAGCAAAUUUCACCAAAGAUGAGAAUUACAAUUAUUUCUGUAUCCUUUGGUACCUUGGCUAAUAGACAAGAGUAAAGAGAAAAGUAAAUGGUGGCCAAAUGAUAACUCCUCUAAGAAAUCCUCCUAUACCAUGCUAGGAAGUUACAAAGAGACAAAAUGGCACAUCAGUUCAUAGAAUGAAAAUGCCUUUGAGAUUAUCCAACGCAACAGUUCUCAAUGACCCAGUAAGAGGGUCUAGAUUCAUAUGAAUAGGUUGCCAUGAGCAGCAAGGUCUCUUGUAUGCAAUUUGUUUCUAAUGUUCAAAGUACUGAAAUCAGCUAAUUAUUUCAUUCUUUUACAAAUUAAAAUGGAUUUGAAAUUAUCCUUUUAAAAAUGUCACACUAACUCACUAGAAUUGCAAAUCAUAAAGAAGUGCAGUGUCAGCUGGUAGGUCUGGUAUUAUAUACACAUCCCCUGAAAAUAUGUUUGGGAAUGAAUCGCGCAUGAAAAUAUAUGGGUGAUAUUUCUUACCGGAAAAAAAAAUGUUUGCAAUCUGUGGAUCUAGGCACCUCCCACAACCUUUCCCAGGAUCAGCAGCAAUUGCGGAAUUCAUAAACAGAAAGUUGACAUGUACAUGGAAUCAGCAAAGGGUCGUAUUCCUGAGGGACAUUUCUCCAGGGCAUGGUGGGGCCUGGAGAAAUGCCUAUGCCAUCGCUAGAGGACACGUUUUUCAUAACUGGAUGCUUCUAGCUCUUGAGCUCUGUGUUUUCUUCUUGUGGACAGUGCCCAAUACCCACUGCCAAAGUUUGUUUUCUCAGUUCAGUUUAUCUAAAGUGGCCAUGCCCCAGAAGUUGACCUUUUCUUUCUUUGGAUGUGCUAAUAUCAUGGAUUAAGCUCCAUAAUUGGUCUUGGUCCAGUGGCUAUUCCCAUAGACCUAGAAGUGUUAACUUAAUUAGCUCAAUUGCAGGAGAACCUUAUUCUUUUACAUAUUCACCUGUUAUGUAGAUGGUUGGAUGGCACUUCACUGUUGCCCCACUUACCAAGAAAUUAAAAUCUAAAUCUGAUUCCAAUUGUUUUGUUGCUGUUUUCAACUGCAUGAUUGUGAUGUCUCUCUCUAUUAUUUAGUGGAGUACAUUUAUACCAAAUCUCAUUUUUAAUCUUAUUUUAUGUAUCUCACUUUGUUAUUUAUAAUUUGCCUAAGUAUAUCAUCUUAACAGCUCUAAACUAUUCUAGGGAUAGAAAAACAUGUGACUAUCUCAAUUUCUUUUUUUUUUUAAGAGUACAAGCAAACCUAACAAAGAUGAUACCAAACCCUUAUAAAUCAAACUCACAAGUUAAAAAAAUUCCAAGUAAAAUUCUGGCAAAUUUAGUCUUGCAGACAUUAUAAACAAUAACAAACCAUGACCACAAGAGCGGAUUCUUAAAAAUGCAAGAAAUUUUUACUACUAGAGAAAUCUGCUGUUACAAUAGAUGCUAUCAAUAGGUUAAAUGAGAAAAUUUCUAUCAUUUUUAUAGGUGACCAAAGUACUUGAUUUAAUAUAAUUGCUGAUAAAAACUCUUAAUGUAACAAACAUAGAAGGUUAAUUAGUUUUAAAAGAUUCUUUUUUAAAAGAUUAAAUAUCCACUUAAUUAUAAAAUUCUCUAUAUAUUUCAAAAUGAGAAAUAAGAAGGAAUAUAAAUUAAUGAUAAUUUUUCUCAAAAGUCUAGCAAAUAUAAUGACAAGGAAAAAAGGUCAUGUGAUUAGGGAAGUGAAACAAAUCUCCAUUUGUCUGUACUGAAAAUUUAAAAGAAUCAACUGAAAAAAGCUAUUAAAACUGUCAAGCAUUUAAUAUAGUAUCUACUUAAAAAUCAAAGUGUACUUGUUAGUCAUAAUCAAUUAGAAAAUAAACAAAAAACACAUAUCACAUUAGCAACUCUAAAAUAGAAAAUAACUAGGACUAAAUAUAAAAAGAAAUUUAUAAGACCACUUUAAAAUAUAUAUAAAAUAAUUUGGAAGAUGACAUUUAAUAAGAAAAUAUUCUAUACUAAUUGACAGAAAGAAUCAAUAUUUUAGAAAUAUAAAUCUCCCCAAAGUAAUCCAACAAUUUAAUGCAACUGAAAUAAAAAUUACUGGGCGAUUCGUUCAGUAAUGUGACAAAAUACUUUAAAAAUUCAUGUGGAAGAAAAAAAAGCAAAAUAGUCAAUGAAUUAUUAAAGUAAUCAAUGUUCCAAAAAGGUUAAGAAUAAUUAUAUCAAAAGAAAAGACUUGAUCAAGUUGCUACAUAAUAUACAAAGCUGUAUACAAUGAAAAAAACUGUAAACAAAAUUAAAUGGCUACAAAUGCAAUGGGAAAACAUCUACAAGACAUAAUUUUUAAAUAUAUAAAGUAGUAUUACAAAUAUGUAGUAAAGACACUGGAUUCCUAUGAAUCCAAUAGACCAAAGGCCCACAAACUUUUUCUGUAAAGGGCAAAUAGUUAAUACUUUUGAUUUUGCAGGUGCCACAGUCUAUUUUGCUACUACUAAACUCUGUCCUUGUAAUUCAAAAGCGGCCAUAGACAGUCUGUAAACAAACAGUCAUGACUGUGUUACAGUAAAACUUUAUUUGUGAAAAUAGGAAGUGGUCCAAAUUUGGCCCACAGAAUAUAGCGUGCCAACGCCUGCAAUAGACCUGUGACAUGUUUGCUGCCUAUAUUCCAGAUACACUUAAAAGCAAGCAUGCUCAACAUGAGGCUUGUUGAGAAACAGGAUGCUCAACAAAUAUAUGCUGAAUGAACAAGUGAAUAAAUAAAAGAAAACAACCCACGAAAACAGAAACUAAAGUCACCAGUAAACAUAUAAAAUUGUUCAAACUCACACAGUGAAAGAGGCAAAUUAAAAUCAUGAUAAAACAUUUGGUUACUCUUGGAUUCACAAGGUCUGCUUGUUUUUUCUUUAAUGAUCAUUCUUAGGUUUGGUAAGGUUAUAGACUAAUGCAUAGCCUCAUAUGCUGCUGGUAGGCUUUUUUACUUUUAUUUUAGUUAUAUACAUAAAUAAGAAAUUAAUUAAUUAGAAAAUAAUAUAAGGAGAUCUGUCUAGCCCUGGAUUGGCAGUCCUCAAAUUAUUUGAUCUUAUUCUUAAAAAUUGUUGAGAACUCCAAAGAAAUUGUGUUUAUUAAUGUUUCUAAUGUUUCUUUACCACAUUAGAAAUUACAAGAGAAACAUUUAAAAUAUUUGUUAAUUCAUUUAAAGUAGUAAUAAUAAAUUCUUUAUAUGUUGCCAUAAAUAACAUUUUUCAUGACAAUAGUUAAAUUUUUGCAAAGGAAAAAUAACAAAAACAAAAAAUGAUUGAGAAGAGCAGCAUUGUUUACAAUUUUGCAUGUCUGGCCUAAUAGAAGUCAACUGAAUUCUCAUAUCUAUUCUCAUUUUGCUUUCAUUCUAUUGUGGUAUGCUUUUUUGUUGAAGUAUGUGAAGAAAAUUAAUCCGCAAACAGUUAUGGCAUUGUAAAAAGGAAGAGUAUUUUAUUAGCCUUUUAUGAUAAGUGUGAAAAUUCUGCUUUGAUACUACACCAAAACUCAACAAGUUGUAGAUUCUUCAAGGACAGUUGCAAUAUGGAGUUUGAAACCCUAUCACUGAACUUUUUGUACCCUGUUACAUUAAAAUCCAUUUGUUUAUCUUGCACUUUCAAUGGAUCUUUUACUCAUGCAUGAUUUUGUAAUACCAUGCAUUGAUUUAAAAAUAUUGGUUCACUGAGUUAUGCAGAUCUUCCAGAUGUAGACACAUUUCAUUAUAUAGUACAAUAUUCAGGAUUCUAUUUAUUACAUCUCCACAGAUCUGAGUAAAGUCUUUAACUAUGGGAAUCUAUCAAGCCCACGAUGGUAUAUAUGAAUUUUCCAAAAUUCUAAUUUUCAUUUGAAAGCUUGAAUUUUAUCAUUGGCGACAAAUACUUUCAGUUGUUUUUGUUGAAGUGACAGACUCUUUAUUCACUUUUGAGAAAAAGUGAAACACCCAAGUCUGAAAAUCAAAGUUUGUUUCUCAGUGACUCUUUCAAGAAAAACUAAAUUAUGUUAUAUGAAGAAAGCAGGUAGUUCAGCUUACAGUUAAUCAGUCACACAAGUGCUUUUCCUCAAGACAACCCUCAAACUUCUAUCUGCAACAGCAGUGCCAUAUGUAUACUUGCCCUUUCGUCACUUGGAAAAUUUUGUGCUUAAUGGUUGAGAUUUAAUUAAAAUAAUUUUUACUGUUUAAUCAAGGACAUUUUUAAGUGGAACUGGCUUAUUUUGUUUUUCUGCAAUUGUAUGGUGCGAGACAUAUAAUGACUACGUGUUCAGGUGCUGCCGCUACCUUGAUUCGUGCCACAGAUUUACUCCUUACUGCUUUUACCAACAGUGCAAAUGUCAACACAGUGAAAAAGUAAUGCCUUAGUAGUAUUAUGAAAAUAAUUUUGGCCUCACAGAUAUCCUACAAGAGGCUUGGAGUCCCCCAGAAUUUCUCGGAUACAUUGAGAACUGUGUCCUAGAUUUGAGAAAUGUUAACGUUUUAUCUUAUUUGCUCCAAAAUUGUUUGUUAAUAAAAUUAAUAUUAUGGAUCCAGCUAAAACUCCUACAUCUCUUCCCUAGUCUCCUUUUGCAGAGAUUAACCGUUAUGUUGAAGUAAGAGUAUUCUUUCUGUACAUGAUUUUGUACUUCCCCUAUGUAUGUAAAGAUCCACAACAGUAUAUUUUUAUUUUGUUUUGAAAAAAUUUUACAUAAAUGAUUCCAUUCUGUAUGUAUGCUUUUACCAAGAUUUUUUCACUCAAUGUUAUGACAUUCUGUUUUUCAGAGAUCUAUGUUGUUAUGUAUAGAUCUAGCUCAUAUAUUUUUCUUGCUGUGUGACAAAUGUAUGAAUUUAUUGCUGUGUGACAAAUAUAUGAAUUCCUGGAUUAACGAAUAUUUAGAUUGUUUCCAAAUUUUUACUAUUUUAAAUAUUUCUUUAAAUAAGGUCACUCUAGGUGAUCAAUUGUUCUAUCUAUAUUGUCAAGUUGUCUCCAACAUGGCUUUAUCAAUUUACAGCAUGGUGUGGUUCUAACCUGGUACUGUCUUUCUGGAGAUAAUUUGGCAGUGCGUAUCAAAUACUUCAUAAAAAGGCGGAGUUGACAUUUCUGGGUCAAAAAUUAUAAGAGUUGACCAUAAUGGUCAUUUGGCCAUCAUUAUUUAUAAAACUGAGAACCUGGAUAACAGCUUCUAGAUGUUUAAUGAUAGGUAAUUAGUUAAAUAAAUGGUAGUAUCUUUUAGUUGAUGAUAAUGUAGUCAUUGUAUAUCCUAAUUGUGUUUAAUUGAUACAUUUUAUAUUUUAUCAAAAUGAGUGAUAGGAAAUUUUAAUUUUCUUCUUUGUGUUUUUUAUUUUCUACUUUUGUUAUUGAGGAAAUAUGUUGUUACCAAAAAAAAAAAAAAAAGGAAGAAAGAAGGGUUGGUGAAUAUUUUGAAACCUCAUCCCAAAUUAAGUGUCAAAUCAGACCAAAAAAGUAGAACAGCAGUUCCCAAAUUUGACAGUGCACAGAUGCAUUAGAGAGCUUGUGGCAACCCCUCAAGGUGUUGAUUUGGUCAGAUUGGGGAUCAAUGACACCCUGAAAUGCAUAAACCUCACAUAUUAAGAAAUACUAAUUUAGAAACUAAUUUGAUCUGAUAUGCCUACAUUGAUGAACCAUAAGGAGUCUUGUAAUUUUCAAUAUUCUGCAGGCAAAAGAAUCAAACAGUGGCUGGGGAAAAGUUCUACUGGUGCCUCUCCUUGUGUCGGCCAAAGCUGAGGGCAGGAGCCUCUGUAACAUCCUGAUGGUGGGGUUGGGGGCAGAGCUCUGUUUUCUAAAAACCUGUCCCAGACUUUACUUUCUUCUCCUUGGCUUAAUCUGCCUCAGACUUUGCUUUCUUUUCCUUGGCUUUGGCAGCCUGCCCUGUAGCAGACAAGGUAAAGCCUGCAGGUGGUAGCUCAGGUGUUCAUCCUCAGUUCUCUCCCAGCCCUCUUUCUUCUCUAACACCUGGGCCACUUCCUCUAUUGAGCAGAGCUUCUCAAAUUUGUGCAUCAGAAUCUUUGGGUGAGCUUUUUUAAACACAUAUUUAUCCCCCUACCCUAGAGCGUCUUAUUCUGUAGGUCUGACAAGGAGCCAGAAAUCUGCAUCUAAAAUAAACUCCCAAGUGUUAGGGAAACUGCUGGUCCAGGGACCACACUGAAGUAGCGCAAAUCAGACUCACUGUGGAGAGCCAGCCUGGGACACAAGGGGGUUGAGUCAUAAAAUGUUAUUCACUGCAAUUUAGAAAUGCAGUAAGAACACUAAACUUAAAACUAUAUCCUCAUUAGGAGGCUAGGCAGAGUUAUUGAUAGACGUGGAAGCAGUAGCAGUAACAGCAUUGCUAGUAGUAGUGGUAAUCCUUAGAAAGCAAUAAUAAUAAAAGACCUAGUGAUAAUAGUAAAAUCAAUAACGAAAUAAAAUAAAUAACUAGGGAGUAUUUUUCCUCCCAUGUUUUGACAAAGCUCUUGAACAUGAGAUAAUCUUUUGAAUGCAAAAAAAGUCUCUUUAAAUGGAUAUAUUACAUUUUCAGUGAAAGCAAGGUCUUUAAAAACAUGCCAGACCUUAUGAUCCAGAAAAAGCUGUUUCUUUUCCUCCUGCAGGGUAUUAUUUAUCUUUGGCUAAUAGCUUUAGCCCAGCCAUUUUUAUAGCCUCACAUGUUAUCAAAAGUGUUUUUAUUGCUUAAUCUAACUACUCCCUUUCUCAACCUAGUGCAUUAAUCGUGCCUUUAGAGGCCAGGUGUAAACUGAAGUCUAUAUAAAAGGGAUGGACUUUUUUUUUAAAAGCUCGUUUGUGUUUUCCUCUUUGUGUUAAAUUAUGAAUGUGAUAAUUGGUGGUUAAUGAGAUGUAAGUACUGUAGUCUCAGACACUUUGGGUUAUUCAUGUCUCUGCACCAUUUUCAUCUGGCCCUCAUUUUCCAAACACCAGACCUGUAAUUAUGCCAAAAAUCUAUCCAAGCCAGAUAAUAUUUUGUUUUUUCUUAUUACUACUUACAGAGCAUGAAGUUGUGGAAAGUGUUGGACUUGCAAAGCUAAUUUUAGUCCCCCAGUGAAAGUUCUGAGGGGCAACUCAAUAAGGUAAAAUUAAAGGUAUAUGAAUCACGGAUUUCAGAGUUUACAGAGACAUUUAGUAAGCAUCUGAUCUAGCCAUUUAGCUUUAGGAUCAACCCCAUUUUGCUGGUGAAUUAGCCAUGGCUUACAACAAUGAAAUAUAUAUAGACCUACGAUUCAACCUGGAGAUCUGUCUGGCCCUACAGCUAGUAGCACUGUGCCUCGUUUGAAGGAGUUGGACGCCUGUCUUUUGCCUUCCUGCAAGGUGUUUUUUUCAUUGCAUCAUGCUAUUGCCAGUCUACCUUGAACUCUUUUUGAGUGUUUUUCAUAAGCUUUUGCUGUUUCAUUUAUGUUUAAUUUGUGUGGUAUCAUUCAAUGACUGUGUCCUUGCAACAGAUAUUUUGAUGUACUAAAUUUGUACACAUACCUGAGUUGGGAAAGGAGAUGCAUUUUGUUUUGCAUAAAAAAAAUCUAGGUCUCAUGUUUACAUUUAAAAUAUCAGGCUUUGUUUCCACUAAAGUGGUAAUCUUUCUAAAAAUGUCCCUCACAUUGAAGGACAUCCAAAAGGCAGUAACUCAUUAGAACCUUGGGUUCAGAUUACAAAUGUGUUUGGCUAGCUCAGUAUUGAAGUUCAAAUUAUCUUGGAAUUAUUUUAAAUAUUUGUACAGGAACACUGAUUAGUUUACUAACGUGUUGCCUAUCCACUAAUAACCACCUUGGCCUAUGGUCAUUAACUCCUAGGGCUCAAGCAAACUCUCAGCAAAGAGAAUUUGCUUCAGUGUUUGAAGCCGUCAUUUGGUGUCUUCACCCCAGGACUUGGAAGUGUUGACUCAGAAAAGGAAUUUGAAAACAGUUUUUAUAACUGCAUUUUAUUCUUUGAGCAGAAGAGUUGAGAGAAAAAAGUUCUGGUGAGGUAACGUCCUCCCCUACCUUCUUCCCCUCCUUUUUUGGUAGUUAAUAUUUUCUGAUUAUUUACAUUCAACUGGAGACCAAGAAUGUGGUAUAAGGAAAAGAAUGUCAGUGUAGAGUCAGCACACCUGGGAUAUGGUUCUGGCUCUGUAUUCAAUGCGUGACCUUAGACAAGUCAUUUAAUUUCUCUGGGUGUUUGUUUCUAUAAAUGAGAAAGUGACAUAGGUCAUUCUUAAGCUGUUUUUCAGCCAGAAGAGUCUGUAAAUAUGUAAAUUUUUCCAAGAGAAGCUAAACUAGCUAGAAGAUCGUAUGAGGGUUACACAGACCCGUGCCUUCCUUAUUUGUUACCUUUUGACAGGGCCAGCUUCAAGGACUGCAACCUGCACAGUCACACAGGGCCUCAAGCUCAGAGGGGCUCUGUACUUGGUUUAAUGCAGUGCUGUCACCAUCUUACAAUUCUCAUUAUUCCUAAACAGGGCCCUGAAUUUUCAUUUUGCUCUGGGCCAGAUAAAUCAUAUAGCUAGUGCUGCCUUUUGGUAAUACAUUUUUUCCCAGUUCAUCUGUUGGUUGAAAAGAAAAAAGGAAUUAUAACCUCAAAUUGGUCACUUUUGUCACCAUUAUGCCCUUCAGGUAGACUGAGGGAGGCAUAAUUUUGACACAAUUAUAUAUGUGGACUUUUGGGGUCAUUUUCUUUUUUUUUUUUUAAUUAUACUUUAUGUUCUAGGGUACAUGUGCACAACGUGCAGGUUUGUUAUAUAUGUAUACAUGUGCCAUGUUGGUGUGCUGCACCCAUUAACUCAUCAUUUACAUGAGGUAUAUCUCCUAAUGCUAUCCCUCCCCACUCCCCCCACCCCACAACAGGCCCCGGUGUGUGAUGUUCCCCUUCCUGUGUCCAAGUGUUCUCAUUGUUCAAUUCCCACCUAUGAGUGAGAACAUACGGUGUUUGGUUUUUUGUCCUUGCGAUAGUUUGCUGAGAAUGAUGGUAUCCAGCUUCAUCCAUCUCCCUACAAAGGACAUGAACUCAUCAUUUUUUAUGGCUGCAUAGUAUUCCAUGGUGUAUAUGUGCCACAUUUUCUUAAUCCAGUCUAUCAUUGUUGGACAUUUGGGUUGGUUCCAAGUCUUUGCUAUUGUGAAUAGUGCCGCAAUAAACUUACGUGUGCAUGUGUCUUUACAGCAGCAUGAUUUAUAAUCCUUUGGGUAUAUACCCAGUAAUGGGAUGGCUGGGUCAAAUGGUAUUUCUAGUUCUAGAUCCCUGAGGAAUCGCCACACUGACUUCCACAAUGGUUGAACUAGUUUACAGUCCCACCAACAGUGUAAAAGUCUUCCUUUUUCUCCACAUCCUCUCCAGCACCUGUUGUUUCCUGACUUUUUAAUGAUCGCCAUUCUAACUGGUGUGAGAUGGUAUCUCAUUGUGGUUUUGAUUUGCAUUUCUUUGAUGGCCAGUGAUGAUGAGCAUUUUUUCAUGUGUCUGUUGGCUGCAUAAGUGUCUUCCUUUGAAAAGUGUCUGUUCAUAUCCUUCGCCCACUUGUUGAUGGGGUUGUUUUUUUCUUGUAAAUUUGUUUGAGUUCUUUGUAGAUUCUGGAUAUUAGCCCUUUGUCAGAUGAGUAGAUUGCAAAAGUUUUCUCCCAUUCUGUAGGUUGCCUGUUCACUCUGAUGGUACUUUCUUUUGCUGUGCAGCAGUUCUUUAGUUUAAUUAGAUCUUUUGGGGUCAUUUUCAAUGACCUAGGUUUCUGAUUGCCCACAUUUUCCCUCUUCUAUGCUUCUUUGCCCCACCUCAAUCCAUUUUUUUAAAAAAUGAGAGUUAAUUACUGGUAUUUACCAAGUAUUUUCAGUCUGUCUAUUCAACAUCAUUAUGUCCAUUGAUACAUAAGCAGUUAUAGUAUAAGAUAGAAGAUACUUUUGGCUUUGAAUUAUUGUUUUGUUGUAUAUUUUUACUUUCUUGCAGAGGCUACAAUUACAAUAGCUUGACAACUAGAGAGAAUUCUUCGGUCUGACGCCACCAGUAGAGGGAUUUCUCUCUAUGUGUUAUGUGGGCUGUUUCCCUCAGCAGCUGGUUUGUUCUGACCAGAUGAGCUCCACUUCCCUCUUUGAGAAGGCCGAGGUGGGUGGAUCACAAGGUCAGGAGUUUGAAACCAGCCUGACCAACAUAGUGAAACCCCGUCUCUACUAAAAAUACAAAAAAAUUAGCCAGGUGUGGUGGCAGGUGCCUGUAAUCUCAACUACUUGGGAGGCUGAGGCAGGAGAAUCGCUUGAACCCAGGAGGCAGAUAGCACCACUGCACUCCAGCCUGGGCGACAGUGUGACACUCUAUCUCAGAAAAAAAAAAAAAAAAGACUUGCUAAAGGUGCUAAGAUGUGCAUUCAUGCAGGGGCCAGCUUGAUUGUCUAUGUUAAUGCUAAUAAAAAUUACUCUGUGACUGCAAGGAACAUAUGGCUUCUUGGCUUACACAAUAUUGUGUGCUAAAGGAUGAAAGAGCAAAAGACGGAAAAAACGUUUUUUAGGUAUGUGCUGAUGGAUGAUGGAGUUUUAUGUUAUGAGUCUGGUUUCAGAAACUUGGAGCAAAUCUCUAAGCAACUAUAUGGCCAAGUUACAUAUCACAUCAAUGGCAAUAAUUUGUUUUGAUGGGCCCCUCUGGGGUGUCUAUUUCAAACUAAUCUUCAAAAUUUUUCUCUUGCAAACCCAGUGUUUGUAAUCUUCCAAGAUGCUCUUUUUGCCCUCAGUUCAUAAUGUUUUAUUCCACUUGUUUAAAAAUUCAUCAGAGCUGACUUUUUAUUAUAUUAACAACAUCUGAAUGUUUUAAAAUAUUUUGUCUUUUUAUGUCACUAAACUGAAUUUAAAUGAUAAUAUCUAUGCUGAGUUCUAAUUGUUUCCCUGGGUCCUGACUUUUAGACUGGGGAGCAUACUGUUUUCAUUUCUUAAGUCACAUAAACUGGUAUUUGAAUUUCCAAUUGUGCUUAAGAAUAGCAAAAAAAGAACUGGUAAAUUUUUUAAAAGAAUGCAGUUGGUCAUUCAACAUUUUUAUAUCUGGUAUUGAUAGCCAGGAAAGCACUAGACACAGCUUCCACUUUCGUUGUAUCCAAUGCAUUGCAUUUUCCCAGCAUUAAAUUUAUAGUUGUGAAACUUUGGGAUUUUAAACGAAAAGAACCAAAGUGAAACUCCUCAAGUAAUUAGAUAAAUGCUUUGGUUCUGUGCAUUUUAUUUCAAAACACCUUUUUGAACACUGCUUUACAAAGAUUUCAAAGAAAGAGCCAUGGAAGCCUAAACACACAGGUUACUUGUGAAAACAGAGGAAAUCGGAGGCCCUAGUUUAGAGCGCUCACCCAGUGGUGCAUAGUUUCUUUCCAGGAAAGGAGGUGCAGUGUCUUCUCACAAGUGUUGGUCUCUACUAUAGAGUGGCCCUGCAGGUGACAAUUAGCAUCACAGUGAAAACUGGCAAGAGUUGGAGGCAACACCUCACUUCAAAGAUGUCAUCUAUUGAAACACUAGGCAGAAACACCCACAGAGUGAAGUGAAUACUGUGGCAUUUUACCCCUUGAAAGGAACUCAGUGUUUUCACCGUUGGCCAAACGUUGUAAUCACCUGCACAAAGAAAAAAUGUCUGGGUUCUACCCACAGAGAUUCUGAUAUAACUGGUCUAGGGUAUGGCCCAGGCAUUGGGAUUUGAGAAAUGCCCCAGAUGAUUUUAAGGGGCAGCCGUAGCUGAGAACUAAGGUCUAUAGUGAGGUAUGUGGGUGUGUGUAUAUAUAGAAAAAAUAUAUAUAUGCCUAUAUAUAUAUAUAUGCCUUGUGGAGAUACAAUUCACAUACCAUACUAUUCACUCAUUAAAAGUGUACAUUCAAUGGUUUUUAGUGUAUUCACAGAAUUGUGUCACCAUCACCACAAUCAAUUUUACAUUUUCAUCACCUCAAAAAGAAAUCCACUAGCAGUCAGUCCCCAUUUCUCCCACUCUACCUCUAGGCAACUACUUAUCUACUUUCUGUCUGUAUACAGUUGCCCAUUCUGGAUAUUCCAUAUAAACGGAACCAUAUAAUUCUACAUUUUGUUUACCCAUUCACCAGUUGGUGGAUAUUUGAGUUGCUCUAACUUUUUGGCUAUUAUGAAUAAUACUGCUAUAAACAUUCAUGUACAAGUUUUUUUGUGGGCAUACAUUUUCAUUUAUCUUGGAUAUAUAUCUAGGAGUAUAAUUGCUGGAUCAUAUGGUAGCUUUAUGUUUAACUAUUGGAGAAACUGCCAGACUGUUUUCCAAAGUGGUUGCGCCAUUUGCAUUCCCUUCACCAGCAUAUAAGGGUUCCAAUUUCUCUACAUCCUUGCCAACACUUGUUUUUAUCUUGUUUUGAUGAUAGCCAUUCUAGUGGGUGUGAAAUGGUAUAUCGCUGUAGUUUUGAUUUGCGUGUACUGCAAAUCAAGUUGAACGUCUUUUUAUGUGCUUUUUGCCCACUUGUUUAUCAUCUUUGGAGAAACUUCUAAUUUAGAUCCUUUGCCUAUUUUCCAAUUGGAUUAUUCGUUUUAUCAUUAUUGAGUUAUAAUAGUCCUUUACGUAUUUUAGAUACAGAUUUCUUAUAAGAUAUAUGAUUUUCAAAUAUAUUCUUCUCUUCUGUGGGUUGUCUUUUCACUUUCUUGAAGGCCUUCACUGAAGCACAAAAGUUUUAAUUUUGAAGAAGUCAAAUUUUAUAUUUUCUUUGUUGCUUGUGCUUCUGGUGUCAUAUCUAAAAAAAGCUUUGCAUAACCCAAGGUCAUGAAAUUUUUCUCCUGUAUUUUCUUCUAGGAGUUUUAUAGUUUUAGCCCUUACAUUUAGGUUUAUAAUCCAUUUUGAGUUAAUUUUUCCAUAUGACAUGAGGAAGGGUUCCAGCUUCAUUCUUCUGCAUGUGGAUAUUCUAGAGUGAGUUUUUAAAAUAGCCUCCUCAUCAAUGUGACAAACUUCAUGGGGCAUGGCUCAUGAGGCAUCUAUGCCAAUAAUAAAUUUCCAGAGAGUUCCAGCUUCCUUCUGCUCUCUGCCAGAGUGUCUAUACACUGGUAUAAAGUCUAAACACACACUUGGAGCUACCAACAAACACAUUUACAUAGUCUCUAUUUAGUAAGCUGAGGUUUCUCUGCUUGCAGGGGGACACUUAGGAAUUAAGUGAAGCGUGAUAUCAGGCAUUAAAGGUUUUCAAAGGAAUUGUUCUUCCUUUAUUGCACGAAUCCACACAAAUACAUUUAAACUACAGUGUGUGACCUGUGAGUCAGGAAGUGCCUUGCUGAAUGCUGUGGUGCUAUUUGAUGAUGUUUCAUUGCUUUCUGCUCCUGCCUGUUUGAGUGAGGAAAGACCCUUCCUGAAAUUUUUGAGUCAGAAGUUACUUCUAGGAAGGUUAUGACAUUUUCUUCUCUGAAACUGCUUAAAAGCAGACGAAGCAUCCCUCCAAAAAGUCCAAAGUAGAGAUGUAUGAUCCAUACCCAAUGUUCUGUGCUGCUGUAGGGAGGUGGCAGGUAGGAUUAGAAACAGUUCCCCAGGAAGUAGGGAAACCCUCAUCAGCCAGGCCACCAGAUGGAGAGCCCAAGUCAAGGAAUAAGUCAAGUUCUUUCCUCUCUUUAGCUCUAAAAGUACUGGCUCUCACUCAGGUAGAUUUGUCUUUCACAAAUGGCCUCUGUACUUCUCUAAUGUCCUUCUGCACUCCUGGCUUAAGAGGGGCACAUUAAUAUAUACUCUAAGAGACUAUGUUGAAACUUCUCUCACAUCCCAUAAAGGCUCUGGGCAAAUACUCUUUUACCUCAAGAAACAAGCAAGGAAAAUAGGCACAGAAUUUUAUAGAUCUGAGUUCAAAUCCUGGCCCCACCACACAACCUCGAUUAUUUUCAGUGAAUUGUUUAACUUCUUUGAGCCUUAUCUUCCCUUUCUAUGAUAUAGAAAUAAAAAUAUCUAUUGAAGAUCAUUGUGGGAUUAACUGAGAAAAACAAAUGUAAAAUUCCUGGACCAAGUUGGGAGCUCAAUAUAUUUUAUUCCUCCCUCCCUUUCAAUACCAAAGGAGAUAUGGUGGACCCCCAGUUUCAAACCUCAUUUUUUCAGUCUUGAAUUCAAAGAUUUUAAAAGGCCAUUAGCAAAAAUGGACAUUGGAUUUACCACUGGACACAUCAGAUCCAUCUCCUACAUUAUUCUGUUCCUUAAGUGGUUGUAAAGUCUUCAUUCUUUGGCAGAGGAUAGGACCUCACCUUUUGGGGUCUUCCUGCCACCUUAAGUAAAACAUUGCUACUGUCCAUGACUUUGCUGAUACGUCAGCAUUUCAGUGAAGUACCCAGCUGUUUAAAACAGCAGGUAUUUAUUUUCUUUACUGUGAAUAUGCAAGGAUGAAAUGUAGCUGCCUGUUUUUGGAAACGCUUUCUUGGUCUAUGUCAUUUGGUUAGGUUAAGCAAUGGAAUGUAUUGUGACCUUGGUCUGUGCCCUGACCUCUCCCAGGUGCCCCUAGAACUUGUUUAUGCAGAUAUUUAUGGGCCAAGAAGCUGAACCUAAGCCCAAACUCCCCUCAGCUACUUUUCUGUGAAAGGUUAAUUGUUCAGCAGGAGUAUUUAUGUGACUGGAAAAAGGCUUUGAGCAAGACGAGUGUGUAAAACUCUGUUCAGCAGAAGUUACUGCAAGGAGUGAUGGGAUCUGGCAUGGUUCUUUGAGUGAUAGUGGGUAUUCAGUCGUCUUAAGGACUUCCAUUGCCAUGAUAUAAAAAUAACUGAUCUUCUCUUUCAUGGGCCUCCCUGAAAUGUUCUGCAGAUUAUGAUGUAAAAUAACAAGCAAGGCAGGGAAGGACUUCCUUCCAAGGACAAUGUAUAGAUUCAAUUAGUGACAUCUGUGUUAUUUGUAUUUGUAUGGAACUAAGUCCAGUUGUUUUCCACAGAAAAAAACUCAGAAGUCUGCUUGAUGAUGUGUCAAAAAUUGGGAACAACACAUUUGAAAACUACAAACAAAUCUGCGAUUUCCUUCUGGUUGGCUGUCCUGCGUGGGUGCCAAGUUCCACACAUGAUUUAAUGAAUAAGAAGGGGGCUUGGAGGCUCAUAGCAAAGGUCCUUGAAGAGAGCAAGAAAAAGUCUUCCCAGGAAAAGUGGACACCUGAGUGAGUGUUACAACGAGAAGGGGGGCAUCCCAGGCAAGGCAGCUACCAAGCACAGGUGUGAAGCUCGCCAGAGAGGCAAACUCCAGCAUUUUAUAUUUCAUCUGCCCCCAGUGACUUCACUGUAGGAAGAGGAAAUGCAGAAAAACAAACGUCUUGAAGACUGAAAGCCUGUUAUUCAAAGAGGUUAGCAGUAGACUGUUGGAAGUAAGGAGAUGUCAGUGAAAAAAGGGAUCCAGAAUGAUUACUAACCUAUGACUCCCAACAGUAUGACAGAAAAUGGCCUUACAGCCUGGGACAAACCGAAGCACUGUCCAGACCGAGAACACGACUGGAAGCUAGUAGGAAUGUCUGAAGCCUGCCUACAUAGGAAGAGCCAUUCAGAGAGGCGCAGCACGUUGAAAAAUGAACAGUCGUCGCCACAUCUCAUCCAGACCACUUGGACUAGCUCAAUAUUCCAUCUGGACCAUGAUGAUGUGAACGACCAGAGUGUCUCAAGUGCCCAGACCUUCCAAACGGAGGAGAAGAAAUGUAAAGGGUACAUCCCCAGUUACUUAGACAAGGACGAGCUCUGUGUAGUGUGUGGUGACAAAGCCACCGGGUAUCACUACCGCUGUAUCACGUGUGAAGGCUGCAAGGGUUUCUUUAGAAGAACCAUUCAGAAAAAUCUCCAUCCAUCCUAUUCCUGUAAAUAUGAAGGAAAAUGUGUCAUAGACAAAGUCACGCGAAAUCAGUGCCAGGAAUGUCGCUUUAAGAAAUGCAUCUAUGUUGGCAUGGCAACAGAUUUGGUGCUGGAUGACAGCAAGAGGCUGGCCAAGAGGAAGCUGAUAGAGGAGAACCGGGAGAAAAGACGGCGGGAAGAGCUGCAGAAGUCCAUCGGGCACAAGCCAGAGCCCACAGACGAGGAAUGGGAGCUCAUCAAAACUGUCACCGAAGCCCAUGUGGCGACCAACGCCCAAGGCAGCCACUGGAAGCAAAAACGGAAAUUCCUGCCAGAAGACAUUGGACAAGCACCAAUAGUCAAUGCCCCAGAAGGUGGAAAGGUUGACUUGGAAGCCUUCAGCCAUUUUACAAAAAUCAUCACACCAGCAAUUACCAGAGUGGUGGAUUUUGCCAAAAAGUUGCCUAUGUUUUGUGAGCUGCCAUGUGAAGACCAGAUCAUCCUCCUCAAAGGCUGCUGCAUGGAGAUCAUGUCCCUUCGCGCUGCUGUGCGCUAUGACCCAGAAAGUGAGACUUUAACCUUGAAUGGGGAAAUGGCAGUGACACGGGGCCAGCUGAAAAAUGGGGGUCUUGGGGUGGUGUCAGACGCCAUCUUUGACCUGGGCAUGUCUCUGUCUUCUUUCAACCUGGAUGACACUGAAGUAGCCCUCCUUCAGGCCGUCCUGCUGAUGUCUUCAGAUCGCCCGGGGCUUGCCUGUGUUGAGAGAAUAGAAAAGUACCAAGAUAGUUUCCUGCUGGCCUUUGAACACUAUAUCAAUUACCGAAAACACCACGUGACACACUUUUGGCCAAAACUCCUGAUGAAGGUGACAGAUCUGCGGAUGAUAGGAGCCUGCCAUGCCAGCCGCUUCCUGCACAUGAAGGUGGAAUGCCCCACAGAACUCUUCCCCCCUUUGUUCUUGGAAGUGUUCGAGGAUUAGACUGACUGGAUUCAUUCUCAUAAUUCCUACAGCACUACUGGGUGUCAUUUCAUUCCAUUGCCUAGCUCUUUUUUGUUUGUUUCUUUGUGUUGGGAGGGAUUAUUUGGGAGGGAAAAGGGAAGUAGUCCUUGGCAUAGACAUGGAUGAAAUUGCCCCUUGAAUGCGGGUACUUGAAACUAUUGCAUUUCGUUCUCCGGUCCUGUGAUGUGAAUGCUCUGAAGGUUUUAUGGUUGUGGAGGUGGGGUGGGGGACAAUCAUUAACUCACCAGCACCAAGCAUCACCAGCUCCCACCCGUCCCUGGUCCAAGACUUGAGUCAGCAAAAUGGCGCCACAGGACACUAAAGAAGCCUUAAAACCAAGAUAAUACGACCACCUCCACCCAAUCCUGAUGUUCGCAGGGCUGAAGUUAACAGAGCACAGACCACCUUUAGUUAGAUGUGGCUUUCAGCCUUUUAGGGAAAGACUCGAACAAAUUUUCAUCUAUUCAAGAGCAUGCUGUUUGCAGCACUCUUUAUGGUCUCCUAGGAGCAUAACUUGGAAUGUACAGGAAUAUUUGUGUCCUAAAAAAAUCAGCUGCCCUUCCAAUAUCAUUUUUAUAACGUUAUGGUUUAAUUCAAGUUAUACAAAGGUGUGACUCAAGGAUGUGCAGGUAUUGACUGAUGGAGGCCAACAAGGAAAAUAUUUUUUUUCAGUGAGCCCAGAGAAAUUAGAAAUCUUCACCAAUGUCAGUGACUGCAUGGUUUCCAAAAAUUCACAUAGUAUUACCUCACAGUAGGAAGGCUUCUUUCCCAUUUAGGCUCAGAGAACACUUUUACAGAAAUCAAACCUAUUUACAGGGUGGCACCCCUUUUCUGUGGCAUCUGAUCUGUCAUCUCCCAAGCUCCUGAAGUUCUUUAUCCAGGUUGUAUCUUUGCUGAGCUGACAACAGAUUUCUCUAUGGAUCAAAUAUUCUAAUCAAGGAAAGAUACGGUGAAACUUCAGUCUUCUUCUGGAGAAAUGCUGAGGCGAGAUUAGUGCAGCUACAUUCUGAGUUGAAGGAAAUGCAGUGUUCUGAGGGCCCCUUUGUGUCCUGAUGGCUGGAGGACGCUUCCUCCUGGUUAGAUCCUCAAGCUCCUUGCCUCAUUGACAAAUGUCUCCUAGUCCCCUUUUUCCCUCUGACUCUGAGGAACUAAAUAGCUUGACUAUCUCUAAACAGAGACUGGCCCUGCCACUGACCCUCCUGUCCCUCUCAUAGCAUACCCUGACAGAUACUCAAUAGAAAACACCUGCAGACCAUGUGCACACUUAACUUUCCUGCCCAACCUGCCUCCCCAACGGCCCAUGCUAGAAUAGCUUGUGCCCAGAAAACAAACAGUGACACUUCAUCUCUUCAGCGUCAGAAAAUGGGCAUAGAAUGUACCCAUGCAAUUGAAUGUAUCUCAUUCUCCACUGGCAUAGUAGAUAUAAACUAUUCCUUUGCCUACCUUUUACUGCCUUAUCCUGGAAAUAUUGGGGAAAAUAAGCCAUAUCAGUGAGAUUUACCUAAAAACAAAGGAAGGAAAGUCACUAUGGAAACCAAGUAGAUGCUUUUUGUAAGUUUGGUGGAGCAUAACUGGCCCAGAAGUCUGGGUGCCUGAGUUCUAGUUCGUGCUCUGUCAACUGGUAGAUUUGUAAUUCUAGGUCUUGGUUUUCUUACCUGGUGAAUAAGUCAUGAUCUCUAAAACCCUUCCUGCCCUUAAUAUUGUCUGAAUUUCAAGGGGAAAAAAAAAAUCUGGUUCCUUUAAUUAUUUUUUUUUAACACUUAAAUUCCUAACUUUAUUAGACAAGAAGUAUGGCCCACUUAACAGUUAAGGAACGUAAAUUUGUUAUUGGCUCGAAAUAAUAAUUUGACACAAUACUAGUCAACCAUUUAGAGGCCUUGGAAAAAGAAGAGGAACAGCACUGAAAAUUCCAAGUAUGAUUGGAAAUUAUCUGGGAGCGGGGAAUUAAAUAUUCAAUGCAUGAAAGCAAUUGUACUGGCUUCUGGGAAAAAGGAAACAAGAACAUUGCUAUGGAACUUGUUACCCAGAGAAAGGAAGUGAAAAGAUUUACAAUUAUAAGCACGAAAUUCAUUGGCAGAUUACCUGCUUUAUCUACAGACAGAUUGUUUUGGGGUUUGGUUUUGUCUAGGCAGCCUCUGGCCAGGCUCCUUAAUUGCUUGCUCUGCUAAUAUUUCAGCUUCCUCUCUUGACUCCUUGAGGAACCAACCGCUCUUUGGAAGACAAACACUUAGCCACCUCUGUGCUCCAGGGUAACCCUGAGAAGCUCUGCUGUCUGGGGCAAGCUUUCUUUCCAAAGGGAAUGAGAGGAAGGCAAGCAGGCAGGGUCCUGCAGCGUCAGGCCUUCUGGGGAAAGUUUCCUCAUUUUGUUUGACAGGGUCCUCAGUACAUCAGACACCCAGAUUUGAAUAUAAGUUCAGAGCCUGAUCUCAAGCUAAAUCAGAAUGCUUUGGGGACUAACCAUGAUCGAGAAUUGGCCAAAUAGUAUGGCAUAUAAACAGCCAUCCAGCCAGCCGCAAGUAAAGGAACGUUUGAUCCUUGGCACCUUAAAUGAUUGAUUGCCUUCAAUAGGCAAACUGCUGGUCUGGAAAUCUCGUUGAAGGCUGAAUACUUCAUGCGGAGUAGGACAAGCCUUAGCCCACCUUCAGGUUGAAAGGAAAGGCCAUAGGACUCAAAAGAUAAUGACUCUGAAACUAAACUCCUUCCUUCUGAAGCUGACAGAGGUACUUAGUGCAUCUCAAGACUCCAUCUCAUAAAACUCAUUUGUGAGGGAUUUGCUCUAGAUUUUUCUAAACAUUUUUUCAUCUAUUGUCCAGACUUGCAAAUCCAGUGUGGACCUGAUGGAGAUACCCUUCACACCUGCGCUCCCACCCCCUCGGCAGGGAGACGUCUCAGUAGAGGAGAACACACCCAUUAUGCUGGGAUUUGUAUUUAUAAAUCACUUCCCUUUUAGGGAUGAGCGGUGUGGGGCGUGUGUGCGUGUGAGUGUAUGCGCGUGCGUGUGUGACCCUCAAGUGUACUUUGCUCAAUUUAGACGUGCAGUAUUUCCAGAAACAAUGAAAAAAGUAAGAUGUUUUCUUCUUUAUGAUUCUGCUCAAAACACCACGUGCCGCCUCAGAGCUUUUUCUAGAGCCUCGGUCCUCAAUGACGCGCUUGACCUGUUGAUGCCUCAGCCCAGCGAAGCCCCUCACCUGUGCCCCGGGCGACAGCUCUUCAGUGUGCAGUGCAGGCCUGGGGUGGACUGCCAGGCCUUCGCUCUGUGCCAGCAACGCCGUUCUUGUUGCUCCUCCAUGAACAGGGGUACAAGCCCUGGCCCCUCCUCGACACUAAGCCCCCCACAGACUCAGCCUCCAAGGAACCGCUGAGCACCCUUGAAGCAUGUCAUUGUCAGUGAUACCUUUUUAUUCUAUGGAACUCUAACCUAUUCGUGUCAUAUUGACCUUUUGCUGCAUGAGUCAUAAAUUAUGAAAUCAGUCUUACAGUUUUUGAAAUGUAGCCAGCAUUUGUAAGGCUAAACCUUUUUCAUGAACUGAAUUUAAGUGAAUAACCAAGCCACAGUUCCUCCUCAAAUGGAGAGUGAUGAUCGACAUUUGAAUCUCUUUGCCCUUUCCAACGGCUAUGGCAUCAGGUUCUAAAAUAAGCUCGUAAUUUUUCCUGUUAUUUUAAUAAUAUGGAAAUAUUAGCAUAGUGUUUCUUUUGAUAGUGAUAGACUAUAAUCCAUAUUUAAAUUUUAUAGAGAAGAAAUUUUAUUGUACUGUGAUGUAGAUAUUUAUUAUCCAGGUAAGGAUUUGCCCGGUGUGUAUUUUUUACAAUUGAGACAUUUUACUUUAAUCUUUAAAAAAAAUGCAUUAAAAACACACUCAAAAAAAAAAAAAAAAAAAAAAAAAAAAAACCAGACUGGGGGAAAAAAGGUUUGGCCUUAUCACAGAAUUUUUACUGUGCUGUAUAAAUGUUUGCAAAUGCGAAAAGUGUGCAUUUAUAGUGUGUUUCCACAUUAAUUAAUGCCGCCUUCAAGAGCAAUAUUGUGCAGGUAAAACGCUGUUUGUGGCUUUCUGUUGCACAGUUAAAGCUGACCCACCCUAUGCACAAGACAAUCAAAUAUAAAUCUGUCCUCCUCAGGAUGCAGAUAAUACUCAUGUAAAUUAUGGAGCACAAUGUAAGACAAAAGGAGACACUUUACAUAUGUAUUGUUGAUACAGAAAUUAUCAGGGCAUGAAUGAGCUGAUGUGACAUUAUGCCACUUCUUUCUUUUGGUUCUCCCUUAUUAACUUGGCAUUUUUAAUUUGACCAUAGAGCCAAAUUAGUUCUCCAUGCUUUCUUCGUAGAAAAUCCUUUUUUUUCCCAUAAUGUUUUCAUGCCCUGAGAAUCAGAAAAAUACUACAGAAUAGAAAAAGAUUUACAGUCAUUGGAAGAUUUGUGUUUUGCAAACAGUGUUAAGUGAUAUUGCUAGAUGGUGAUAUUUUUUUCAGCCUAAAACUCUGUUGAAAUCUGUGAUCAAAAUGUUUUAAACUAUCCAAAAAAAAUUUGUAUAUUUGGGAAAAAUGGAUUUUUACAUAGCUUUUGUAUGCAGAUAUAAAACUGUAAUUAUGAAUAUAGUGGGCGUAGAUAAACUCAUAAGCUUAAAUUCUAAAAAAGAAAAAGCUUAUAACAGAUAUAUUUUCCUGUCUCUUUCUUUAAAUAUUAUUAUUUUCUACAUAGGCAAAGAGUUGCCUGCUCUUCUCACUUCAGCUGCUGCCAAAAGACGGAACCACGGAUGUAAGGACAUUUAUUUCAUAAAUAAACAUCUACUAGAAUAAGCAAAUUUACUUGAGAAGAAACUAUGGAGGGAGAGAAGAAACUAAGUAAAAUGCUGAUGGGGGGUUACCUCUUUGGAAGGGGCCACAAAGAUGAAGGGAGGAGAGAGGUGAAGUUUUGCAGCUCAAGGACAACAUUCAUCUUCUCAUCUCAAAUUAUUCAGGAAUAUUACUAAUGGAAUUAUGUUAACAUCAGCUGCCAACAUAUAUCUCAAUCUCUGUUGCCCUGAACACAUGUUAAUUGAGAUUCUUUCUAUGACAAGUAACAAAAAGCUAACUCAAACUGGCUUAAGCAGAAAGCUAAUUAUUGACUUUAAUAUCUGGGAUCUAGGGUAUUGCAUACCAAAGCUUCAGGCAUGGCUGGAUCUGGGUGCACUUACUCAGUAUUCUCAGGAAGCUCCUUUUUUUGUCAUUCAUGUAGACUUAACAUUCACAUGGCCUUUCACCUUACGGUGGCCUCCAAUAGCUCCAGGAUGAGCUUUACAGCUCCAAAUAUAGUGAAAGGAGAAUUUCUUUUCUCCAACAAUUCUAAUGAAAAUUCUGGCCUAAUUCUCACUGGCCCAAGUUCAGUCAUGUGCCCAUUCCUGAGCCAAUCACUGUGGUGAGGAAAACAGAUGCAUAACCAACCUUAUCCUCAGGAAUCCUGGAACUGGGUGAGGGGAAAGAGGGACAGUCAGCUUCAUCUAAACUAUGGACUGAGAGUUGAGGCAAGAUGAUUCCUGAAAGAAAAUUCUAAGUCUUGCUGCUAUAAGUGGAAGAGAAUGGUGGGCAAGCAAAAGCAACCAGUGCCCACACCAAAGGUAAAUCUAAAACAACAUCCCAUUUCAGUACAGCAAGCGGUUCUCCUUCACACAGAGGAAGCUCAUCUCCAAGUUUUUAUUUGGCCAGGACAUGAACCAAAUAAACACCUUCCAAAGAAA